AAGAGGUACCAGGCAGCACCAACUAGCACACAGCCAGCAUUAGGAGGCAGUAGUAGAGAGAUAACUAUUGUCAACAGUUCCAGUUUGAUGUCUAGUGAGAUAGAUAGAUAGAGAUGUGCCAAGAGAGUAAAUCACGGCAUUUCUGUAUGUCUGACUAUGGAAUAUUCUUCAGAAAUCACUGAGACCAUUUAUUUUACAUUGGAAUUUCAUCUUGAUCUAAGAUCCAUCAACUUUAGUAGGAUUGCUUGGAAAUGGAUGAUAACUGAAAUUUGCUGUCAACUUAGAAACUCCAUCUGUGAUCACUAUUAUCACCUCCUCACCGCCAAACCUCAAACCAAAGCUGUGCCUUCUGAAUCCAUUUGUGCACGGGCUGUACCCAGGGGCAGCGGUGCUGCUUGGAUGAGCCCCAGUGGAAACGCGGGAGGCAGUGGAGAGGUCUCCUGCAAGUGUGCGAGCACACAGCACCAAGAAGGAAUGCACCUUUGCUGGCAGCGUCGGAUGGGCGUUUCUGACAGCACUGCAGGAAGUACAUGCUCAGUUCCACAGGUUUAGAAGCAGCAAUGCCCUUCUUGCCUGGGAUUGGGAUGAUGCAGCUGAGACAGCCUUCCUGGUAGCCAAGUAGGCUAUUCAGCAAGCACAAGCCCUAUGGGUAGUUGACCAGAGGUGCCCAUUUAAGCUAGAUGUGCAUGUGACCACAGAUAGUUUCAGUUAGGGCCUAUGGCAGUGCAUGAGUGCCUGAGUAUGCCAGUAGGCUUUUGGUCCCAAUUAUGCAAGGGAGCUGAGCUCCAGUAUUCCUUGAUACAGAAGCAGUUAGUAAUAAUAGGAUGGGUGUGUUCAUGGAUAACCACCCCCUGGACAGGGAAAGCAGUUAGUAACUGUAUAUACUGCCCUUCAGGCUCAUAAGAGCAUGGCAGGAAUGGCUACAAUCAUCAGGCAGACAACUUUCCCAACAGUGGGGUGGGUACACUCGUGGGUAAUGACCCCAUCGACUGGGACAGCACAGACAUCCACUUUAGCAAAGUGGGGAGCCUACUUACAGCAGUAAAGUACACUGAUUACAAGUCCCUUAGCAGUAGAGUUACAGGAAGUCUUGGGACCUGUAGUCCUAAUGCCAAGUAAGGCCAUGGGGCCUGAGGCACCCCUAAACCCUAAGCCUUCAUCAUUAGGAAGGGCAUUCUCCCAUUCCUAAUAGGGCUUGGUACACAGAUAUGUGUAGGCAGGGAGCUACUGCUGCCUGGAUUGCUGCCACAGUCCAGCCUAGUACUAACACCAUAUGGGUUAAAACCAGGUGUAGGCAAAGUAGCUAAUGAGCUGCACUCAGGGCAAUGUGAACAGUAAUCACCAAUGUUGCAACACCUAUGGUAAUCUGUGCCAACAGCCGAGCAGUUUAUUGAAGCUUAUGUAUGUGAUGGGCUUGUGUGCCCAGAGCCUAUGUAUAAGGCUUAUGUGUCAGGCCUAUGUGCCCAGAAGCCUAUGUGUAUGUAUCAGGCCUGUGUGCCCAAAGCUUAUAUGCCAGGCCUGUGUGCCAAACCUGUGUAUAAAACCUGUGUGUCCAGGGCCUAUGUUUCCCUCAGCCUAGGGGGUGGAGUGUAAGGUACAUGGAUGUGCUUUGGUCAAGGAAUAGGCCAAGGUGGAUAUCCAAGCGAGUUUGGUGCGUGAGUGUGCACCUCCACUUGUUAUAUAACUUGUUUGUGUAAGUUCAUACUUGGCUCUGAGCCACUAUUGCUGUAAAAGGUAGAACUGCCCUGUCGACACUGUGCACAAGAGACAUGGCUCUUGGGGCUCGGCUCAGCUCAACAUGGCUUGACAUGGCGGGCGUGCUGGCGUCCACAGAAAGAGAGAGUCAGGGCUGUCCAUAUUUGCAGAUGCUCCCUGGGGAGCCAGGAUACAGCUUGGAUUGCUUGUGCCCAGAGAAAGAGUUAAGCUGUUGACCCUGAGGCCAAGGGAGAGCAGGCCAUACAGCUGCAGGUGUCGGGGCAGCAGGGGCCACAGAGCGGGAGCAGACAGCCGAGACACAGGCGAACAGUGUAGAGAGCUAGCGUGAGAAAGCUGUUGAUGAGAAGUGCUGCUGAAUAAAAUCAUCUUUCACCUGCCUACGGCCCCCCGAGUGUUCUUUCUGCUUGCCCACCCACUCCCUCCAGACCUCAUCAUGACCUUUGGCAUAGUCGUGAACCUGAUACAGGCUCAUUUGGCGGUAAUGAGAUAUGUGAUAACUGUUUUAGGUUUAUAUGACCCUCCUCUCCUUUCCCUCCCCCUAAAUAUGUGUGUGUAUGUAUACAUAUAUAUUAUGUAUAUACUGUAUUCCUUUGUUUCUUUGUCUACUAAAACCAACCAUAAAGGAGGGAGCUGCCUUCAAUACCUAAAGUAUAAGAAGGGUGCCGGGGAAUGUCAUAAUGGAGGCUUUCCCAACUGAAUUUGAAUUAUUUCACUAAAGAGAACAUGAGUUGACUCAGCCCUUUCCUCACAGGAGGGAGGGUUCAAUUCCCCUGACUUCACACACUCACUCCAUAAGGCCUGCUUUGGCAAAACUGCCACAGGGGCCUGUGGAGCUGACUCUGGUCCUACCUGGUUUCAGUAGAAGGUCCACUUUUUGUUUUUCUGUUUAAAAAAAUAUGUCCUAUGUGUCCUCAGAAAACUGUACUGGAAGAGUGGGUGGAAGGAACUUGUAUAGGUCAGCUUCCAACACUUUGGAAUAGAUUAAAAAGAGAAUCUUUUAAAUGAAAACUUAAAAAAUAACAAAUAAAAGGGCAAUAUAACAACCGGGCUGUAGAGAAGACAGUGUCUCAGGUAUUACAGAGGCCUAAAGAGAACCUGUGAGGAAGACAAUUAUGAACCUUACCUCAAAUUGUAGUAGCUUAGUUAAUUAAUUAGUAUUACAGCACUUAUGACCAAUGAAGGAUAGAUGUUUGUAAUACGUAAUGUUUUCAUAUAAAUAAAAAGUCACAAAGGACUCAAAACACAAAUGGCAAAUAGGCAAAAUAUUUAAGGGAUACCUCAAAAGUGAUAGAAUAUGAUUAGUAAAUAUUUUUAAAACAAGUUCAGCUUUACUAGAAAGAAAAAAUGAAUUAAACAAUGUUGUAUCAUAUUUUGCUUAGCAUAUCAGCAAACAUUUUAAAAGUCUAUAAACCAAAGUUGUUGCAUUGUAGUGCAAAAAUAAAUAUUUGUCAGAUGACUCAAUAAGUGGAGAGAUGGAUUGAUGACUAUUAGGGAAAACAUCACAUACAAAACCAUGGUUGAAAUCUAUGCAUAUGAAUUAAGGUACAUAUAGAUGCAUGGAAAAGUACUUGUGGGAUGAUAUUCAUUGCUCUUUAGGUUCCUUGUCUGUAAAAUGAAAAUAAAUGCAUUACUUAGGGUUCUUUUGUAAUUUUUCCCUAAUUUUCUUUAUCCCCCAAGUUUCUGUUAUAGUGUUAAAUUUCCUGUAUUUUUGAAAUAAAACUGUAAAAUAAGGGUUUAAAACUGUUUAAAAAUGGGAAAUUGGACAUAAAUUACUGUGGUGGACUGGGAGACUAGACAGAGUUCGAAGAAUGGUAAUAGAAGAGCUUGGAUCCCACAAUUGCCUGUAGUACAAAUUAACGUAUUAGCUAUACCUAAACUUGAAAGGCAGACUAUGGGGACUGAGCCCUGUAACUAUAAUCCAAGUCUUAGGGUCUAGUGGCAAGAUUUUCAGGUCAAUAGGAAGUAGUCCAACAUGAUCCAUUUGAGAAGGACAUCCUGAACAAUGAGAAUUCUAUUUGUGAUUUAUCUCUACUGUAGCUGCAUAUUCACUGAAAUAUCUUUACUCUUAAUGAAGCUUCCUUGUGCAUUUGAAUCAAUAGAGAAGGCUGACCUGGAAUGGAAAGGAUGAGGGGAAGCAGCCCUGAGAAACAAACCAGAGAGAGAAUGGGAAAGGCCAGGACUUGUAAGUUGAAAGAAAACUGAGACAUAGCAGUAGUGAAGAGUUGGGAAGUAGAGCUGCUUGCAUCGUCGAGCACCUAGAAGCUCUAUGCAGUGUGGCUAAAAGUGUGCUCCUAUUUCAGAACUACCAGAGUUCUUUCUAAAAAUGUGGAUUGCUGGGCUUAACUCAGAAAUACUGAAUCCCAGUCCCUGAGGAUGUGCAUUUUAAAUGUUUCAAAGUGAUUCUCAUGCACUUUAGAAAGGUUUGAGAACAAUCACACAUCAGCAUGCUUAAGAAACAUCAGGAAGCUUAUAAAGAAACUAUGUAUUCCCGGAUCGGAUCCCACCACUACAGUUUCUGAUGCACUGAAGCUGGGAUGCUGUCAGAGUCUAUAUUCUCAGCAAGCAUCUUGGGUUUUUGAGGCAGGUCGUUUACAGAUUAUACUCUGGGAAACAAUGUUACAGGUUCUUUGAAUAUAGUUAAAUAUUGGCAUAAAAGAAUCAGAUGACCAGACUAUGAUUUGAAAUUAAGCACAGCAUCAGUAAUGGCACAUUAAUUUCUUCUUUGCUUAUUUAUUUAUGUUUAUGACAGUCCAAUCCUGGUGAAUUUGUUUAACAUUUAAAUAGACAUAAUGUGAGAAUUUUGUGAAAUAAUCUUGUUCUUCCCCACACUAUCACUAUGGGUUAUAACAGCAGGGAGUGACUUUUGUGAGCUCACUUCCAGAAUGGAAGAAGUGAUUUCACCUGAUGAAUAAACCUCCCAGCAUUCUUUAACAGUUGGGUGCAGCUGAAACCUGCAUCAGGAGUAGCUAGUCUCAUAGUAUCAAACACCUUCUUUCUAGCUGACACAGCUUUUAAGACUGGAAACCUGAACAAAGUGAGAAAGAACUAGGCUCCCGAAAAAAAGAAAAGGAAAAAAGAAAGUUGAGUUCUCUUACUGGCUCCAGAAGGAACUCCUAAAACCACUCCAUCGCAGAAGCAACAGGGACGCAAAUCCGUGGAGUCUUCAGCCCCUGAGUGUGCUGCUCUCACAGGCUAAGCUGCAGCUCCAGGGAGAUGAGCAGACACUACAUGGAGUUAUGUGGAAAUGAGAGAGAUUCAUGAAACCCCUCCUCCAGGAAAGAAUGUCUUUCACAGAUGGAGCUUUGCUUCUGGUUUGCACAGGACAGCGACAAUGUGGCAGAGCCAUGCCUGCCCUUCCUGCUCUUUCCAGUGAUUCACAGAACUUCUGAACAGUGAUGCUUGCCUUGGAUUUUCAGGUUUUCAUCCUGAUACUUGUUUACUUUUCUGGGGCAGAAAAGCUUGCACUAAUUGCUCUCCAUGGUGGCUAAUUUUUUCAAGAGCUUGAUUUUACCUUACAUUCAUAAGCUUUGCAAAGGAAUGUUUACAAAGAAAUUGGGAAAUACAAACAAAAACAAAGAGUAUCGUCAGCAGAAAAAGGAUCAAGACUUCCCCACUGCUGGCCAGACCAAAUCCCCCAAAUUUUCUUACACUUUUAAAAGCACUGUAAAGAAGAUUGCAAAGUGUUCAUCCACUCACAACUUAUCCACUGAGGAAGACGAGGCCAGUAAAGAGUUUUCCCUCUCACCAACAUUCAGUUACCGAGUAGCUAUUGCCAAUGGCCUACAAAAGAAUGCUAAAGUAACCAACAGUGAUAAUGAGGAUCUGCUUCAAGAGCUCUCUUCAAUCGAGAGUUCCUACUCAGAAUCAUUAAAUGAACUAAGGAGUAGCACAGAAAACCAGGCACAAUCAACACACACAAUGCCAGUUAGACGCAACAGAAAGAGUUCAAGCAGCCUUGCACCCUCUGAGGGCAGCUCUGACGGGGAGCGUACUCUACAUGGCUUAAAACUGGGAGCUUUACGAAAACUGAGAAAAUGGAAAAAGAGUCAAGAAUGUGUCUCCUCAGACUCAGAGUUAAGCACCAUGAAAAAAUCCUGGGGAAUAAGAAGUAAGUCUUUGGACAGAACUGUCCGAAACCCAAAGACAAAUGCCCUGGAGCCAGGGUUCAGUUCCUCUGGCUGCAUUAGCCAAACACAUGAUGUCAUGGAAAUGAUCUUUAAGGAACUUCAGGGAAUAAGUCAGAUUGAAACAGAACUUUCUGAACUACGAGGGCACGUCAAUGCUCUCAAGCACUCCAUCGAUGAGAUCUCCAGCAGUGUGGAGGUUGUACAAAGUGAAAUUGAGCAGUUGCGCACAGGGUUUGUCCAGUCUCGGAGGGAAACUAGAGACAUCCAUGAUUAUAUUAAGCACUUAGGUCAUAUGGGUAGCAAGGCAAGCCUGAGAUUUUUAAAUGUGACUGAAGAAAGAUUUGAAUAUGUUGAAAGCGUGGUGUACCAAAUUCUAAUAGAUAAAAUGGGUUUUUCAGAUGCACCAAAUGCUAUUAAAAUUGAAUUUGCUCAGAGGAUAGGACACCAGAGAGACUGCCCAAAUGCAAAGCCUCGACCCAUACUUGUGUACUUUGAAACCCCUCAACAAAGGGAUUCUGUCUUAAAAAAGUCAUAUAAACUCAAAGGAACAGGCAUUGGAAUCUCAACAGAUAUUCUAACUCAUGACAUCAGAGAAAGAAAAGAGAAAGGGAUACCAUCCUCCCAGACAUAUGAGAGCAUGGCUAUAAAGUUGUCUACUCCAGAGCCAAAAAUCAAGAAGAACAAUUGGCAGUCACCUGAUGACAGUGAUGAAGAUCUUGAAUCUGACCUCAAUAGAAACAGUUACGCUGUGCUUUCCAAGUCAGAGCUUCUAACAAAGGGAAGUACUUCCAAGCCAAGCUCAAAAUCACACAGUGCUAGAUCCAAGAAUAAAACUGCUAAUAGCAGCAGAAUUUCAAAUAAAUCAGAUUAUGAUAAAAUCUCCUCACAGUUGCCAGAAUCAGAUAUCUUGGAAAAGCAAACCACAACCCAUUAUGCAGAUGCAACACCUCUCUGGCACUCACAGAGUGAUUUUUUCACUGCUAAACUUAGUCGUUCUGAAUCAGAUUUUUCCAAAUUGUGUCAGUCUUACUCAGAAGAUUUUUCAGAAAAUCAGUUUUUCACUAGAACUAAUGGAAGCUCUCUCCUGUCAUCUUCGGACCGGGAGCUAUGGCAGAGGAAACAGGAAGGAACAGCGACCCUGUAUGACAGUCCCAAGGACCAGCAUUUGAAUGGAGGUGUUCAGGGUAUCCAAGGGCAGACUGAAACUGAAAACACAGAAACUGUGGAUAGUGGAAUGAGUAAUGGCAUGGUGUGUGCAUCUGGAGACCGGAGUCAUUACAGUGAUUCUCAGCUCUCUUUACAUGAGGAUCUUUCUCCAUGGAAGGAAUGGAAUCAAGGAGCUGAUUUAGGCUUGGAUUCAUCCACCCAGGAAGGUUUUGAUUAUGAAACAAACAGUCUUUUUGACCAACAGCUUGAUGUUUACAAUAAAGACCUAGAAUACUUGGGAAAGUGCCACAGUGAUCUUCAAGAUGACUCAGAGAGCUACGACUUAACUCAAGAUGACAAUUCUUCUCCAUGCCCUGGCUUGGAUAAUGAACCACAAGGCCAGUGGGUUGGCCAAUAUGAUUCUUAUCAGGGAGCUAAUUCUAAUGAGCUAUACCAAAAUCAAAACCAGUUGUCCAUGAUGUAUCGAAGUCAAAGUGAAUUGCAAAGUGAUGAUUCAGAGGAUGCCCCACCCAAAUCAUGGCAUAGUCGAUUAAGCAUUGACCUUUCUGAUAAGACUUUCAGCUUCCCAAAAUUUGGAUCUACACUGCAGAGGGCUAAAUCAGCCUUGGAAGUAGUAUGGAACAAAAGCACACAGAGUCUGAGUGGGUAUGAGGACAGUGGCUCUUCAUUAAUGGGGAGAUUUCGGACAUUAUCUCAAUCAACUGCAAAUGAGUCAAGUACCACACUUGACUCUGAUGUCUACACGGAGCCCUAUUACUAUAAAGCAGAGGAUGAGGAAGAUUAUACUGAACCAGUGGCUGACAAUGAAACAGAUUAUGUUGAAGUCAUGGAACAAGUCCUUGCUAAACUAGAAAACAGGACUAGUAUUACUGAAACAGAUGAACAAAUGCAAGCAUAUGAUCACCUUUCAUAUGAAACACCUUAUGAAACCCCACAAGAUGAGGGUUAUGAUGGUCCAGCAGAUGAUAUGGUUAGUGAAGAGGGGUUAGAACCCUUAAAUGAAACAUCAGCUGAGAUGGAAAUAAGAGAAGAUGAAAACCAAAACAUUCCUGAACAGCCAGUGGAGAUCACAAAGCCAAAGAGAAUUCGUCCUUCUUUCAAAGAAGCAGCUUUAAGGGCCUAUAAAAAGCAAAUGGCAGAGUUGGAAGAGAAGAUCUUGGCUGGAGAUAGCAGUUCUGUGGAUGAAAAGGCUCGAAUAGUAAGUGGCAAUGAUUUGGAUGCUUCCAAAUUUUCUGCACUCCAGGUGUGUGGUGGGGCUGGAGGUGGACUUUAUGGUAUUGACAGCAUGCCGGAUCUUCGCAGAAAAAAAACUUUGCCUAUUGUCCGAGAUGUGGCCAUGACCCUGGCUGCCCGGAAAUCUGGACUCUCCCUGGCUAUGGUGAUUAGGACAUCCCUAAAUAAUGAGGAACUGAAAAUGCACGUCUUCAAGAAGACCUUGCAGGCACUGAUCUACCCUAUGUCUUCUACCAUCCCACACAAUUUUGAGGUCUGGACGGCUACCACACCCACCUACUGUUAUGAGUGUGAAGGGCUCCUGUGGGGCAUUGCAAGGCAAGGCAUGAAGUGUCUGGAGUGUGGAGUGAAAUGCCACGAAAAGUGUCAGGACCUGCUAAACGCUGACUGCUUGCAGAGAGCAGCAGAAAAGAGUUCUAAACAUGGUGCCGAAGACAAGACUCAGACCAUUAUUACAGCAAUGAAAGAAAGAAUGAAGAUCAGGGAGAAAAACCGGCCAGAAGUAUUUGAAGUAAUCCAGGAAAUGUUUCAGAUUUCUAAAGAAGAUUUUGUGCAGUUUACAAAGGCGGCCAAACAGAGUGUACUGGAUGGGACAUCUAAGUGGUCUGCAAAAAUAACCAUUACAGUGGUUUCUGCACAGGGUCUACAGGCAAAAGAUAAAACAGGGUCUAGUGAUCCAUAUGUUACAGUUCAAGUUGGAAAGAACAAAAGAAGAACAAAAACCAUUUUUGGAAAUUUGAAUCCAGUAUGGGAUGAGAAGUUUUAUUUUGAGUGUCAUAACUCCACAGAUCGAAUCAAAGUCAGAGUAUGGGAUGAAGAUGAUGAUAUUAAAUCCAGAGUCAAGCAACAUUUCAAAAAGGAGUCAGAUGAUUUUCUGGGACAAACAAUUGUAGAAGUGAGGACCUUGAGUGGAGAAAUGGAUGUCUGGUACAACUUAGAGAAAAGGACAGAUAAGUCAGCUGUAUCUGGGGCCAUACGAUUGAAAAUCAAUGUGGAGAUAAAAGGAGAAGAGAAGGUUGCUCCAUAUCAUAUUCAAUAUACAUGUUUACAUGAGAAUCUGUUCCAUUACUUGACUGAAGUGAAAUCUAAUGGUGGAGUGAAAAUCCCAGAAGUCAAAGGGGAUGAAGCCUGGAAGGUUUUCUUUGAUGAUGCUUCCCAAGAAAUAGUUGAUGAAUUUGCUAUGCGUUAUGGAAUUGAAUCCAUUUAUCAAGCUAUGACGCACUUUUCAUGUCUGUCUUCUAAAUACAUGUGCCCCGGUGUCCCUGCCGUCAUGAGCACCUUGCUGGCUAAUAUAAAUGCUUUUUAUGCUCACACAACAGUUUCAACAAACAUACAGGUUUCUGCCUCAGAUCGAUUUGCUGCUACCAACUUUGGUAGGGAAAAAUUCAUAAAACUACUGGACCAGUUACAUAACUCUUUGAGGAUUGAUCUGUCAAAGUAUAGGGAAAACUUUCCUGCAAGCAAUACUGAAAGACUGCAAGACCUGAAAUCAACUGUUGACCUGUUAACAAGUAUCACCUUUUUUAGGAUGAAGGUUCUGGAGCUGCAAAGCCCCCCAAAAGCGAGCAUGGUGGUGAAGGACUGUGUAAGGGCUUGCCUGGAUUCUACAUACAAGUAUAUUUUUGACAACUGCCAUGAACUCUACUCCCAGCUAACAGACCCGAGUAAGAAACAGGAUAUUCCUCGUGAAGAUCAGGGACCAACCACCAAGAAUUUGGAUUUUUGGCCCCAACUUAUUACACUGAUGGUUACUAUUAUUGAUGAGGAUAAAACUGCCUACACACCUGUCCUGAAUCAGUUUCCUCAAGAGCUGAACAUGGGAAAAAUAAGUGCCGAAAUUAUGUGGACUCUUUUUGCUCUGGAUAUGAAAUAUGCAUUAGAAGAACAUGAAAAUCAGCGGUUAUGCAAGAGCACCGAUUAUAUGAAUUUGCAUUUCAAAGUUAAAUGGUUUUAUAAUGAAUAUGUGCGUGAACUUCCUGCCUUCAAGGAUGCUGUUCCUGAAUACUCCUUGUGGUUUGAACCUUUUGUCAUGCAAUGGCUAGAUGAAAACGAAGAUGUGUCAAUGGAAUUCCUUCAUGGAGCACUGGGAAGAGACAAAAAAGAUGGAUUCCAGCAGACAUCUGAGCAUGCUCUCUUUUCUUGCUCCGUGGUUGAUGUCUUUGCUCAGCUGAAUCAGAGCUUUGAAAUUAUUAAGAAACUGGAAUGCCCUAAUCCUGAAGCAUUAUCUCACUUAAUGAGAAGAUUUGCAAAGACUAUCAAUAAAGUGCUGCUCCAGUAUGCUGCAAUUGUAUCAAGUGAUUUCAGUUCACAUUGUGAUAAGGAAAAUGUGCCCUGUAUCUUGAUGAACAAUAUUCAACAAUUGCGGGUCCAGCUGGAAAAAAUGUUUGAAUCCAUGGGAGGGAAGGAGCUAGAUUCUGAAGCUAGUACUAUUCUAAAAGAACUUCAGGUUAAGCUCAGUGGGGUCCUGGAUGAGCUCAGCGUCACUUAUGGUGAAAGUUUCCAGGUUAUAAUUGAAGAGUGUAUAAAACAGAUGAGUUUCGAACUAAAUCAAAUGAGAGCAAAUGGAAACACCACAUCUAAUAAGAACAGUGCAGCAAUGGAUGCAGAGAUUGUGUUAAGAUCUCUUAUGGAUUUUUUGGACAAAACAUUAAGUCUCUCAGCAAAAAUCUGUGAGAAAACAGUCCUAAAGCGAGUUUUAAAAGAGUUAUGGAAGCUAGUUCUCAACAAAAUAGAAAAACAAAUUGUUCUUCCUCCUCUGACAGAUCAAACAGGACCCCAGAUGAUUUUCAUUGCAGCUAAAGAUCUUGGACAAUUAUCCAAACUGAAGGAGCACAUGAUUCGAGAGGAUGCCAGGGGUCUGACGCCAAGACAAUGCGCUAUAAUGGAGGUAGUCCUGGCUACCAUCAAGCAAUACUUUCAUGCAGGAGGAAAUGGCCUGAAAAAGAAUUUCUUGGAGAAAAGCCCAGAUCUUCAGUCUCUGAGAUAUGCUCUCAGUCUUUAUACCCAAACUACUGAUGCCUUGAUAAAGAAAUUCAUAGAUACUCAAACCUCACAGAGUCGUUCCUCCAAAGAUGCCGUGGGUCAGAUAUCUGUUCAUGUGGACAUCACUGCCACCCCAGGAACGGGAGAUCAUAAAGUCACUGUAAAAGUGAUUGCUAUUAAUGACCUAAACUGGCAGACCACAGCAAUGUUCCGCCCCUUUGUGGAAGUUUGUAUACUGGGACCCAACCUUGGAGACAAGAAGAGAAAACAAGGCACAAAAACAAAAAGCAACACAUGGUCACCAAAGUACAAUGAAACAUUUCAGUUCAUUCUCGGAAAGGAAAAUCGACCAGGGGCUUAUGAACUUCAUCUCUCAGUUAAGGAUUACUGCUUUGCCAGAGAAGAUCGAAUUAUCGGAAUGACAGUCAUUCAGCUACAGAACAUAGCAGAAAAGGGAAGCUAUGGGGCAUGGUAUCCUCUUCUGAAAAAUAUCUCUAUGGAUGAAACUGGUUUGACUAUCCUUAGAAUACUCUCUCAGAGGACCAGUGAUGAUGUGGCUAAAGAAUUUGUAAGACUUAAAUCUGAAACAAGAUCUACUGAAGAGAGUGCUUGAAACAAACACUGCAAGCUAAAUACAUAACUAUAAUUGUUUGACUACUGCAUGCAUGUGCAAAUACAUGGGAAUGUUUAGUUCACUACAUUUCAAUGUUUGCCAGUACUCAUGUACGAUGUCUACAAGGUAUGUAAAAAACCUGCUGAACUUUUAUACCAAUUCUGGUCUUUGGGAAAUCAGUGUUCCAUGAAGUGCCAAAAUUAUGAUGUAAAGUGAAAUAUCAAGAACACCUUUUAACAUGUUUAUUUUGUUUCUUUACCCAUUUCACAUUCAUUAAACAUAAUUUUUAAAAACUAGUCUUUUGAGUUUGCCCAUCAGUUGUCUUUGUUAAAUGAGAUUAUAUUGCCCAUAGAUCAGAAAACAUUUAUUACUCAAUUUCCAUUUUAUUUACUUACCUCAUUAUAGAUGUCUUACAAAUACCCUUUUCUACCAUAACUAGAAAUGCAGUCACUUCUAGAAAGCAUUUGUAAUUUUAUAGUCGCAGAUAUUGUGAUUUUUGCAUACACAUUAAAAUAGAAAAGGUGGGAAAUAUUUUCUGCUGACCAGUUUCCAACCUUUCUGAAAUAUCACUGUGAAGAAAUGCUGUUAAAGCAAACUUACAUAAAGCAAUGCUAGAGUUUGUUAACAAUGUUUGAUAUAUAUUGACAAAACUUUGUUCUCUAAAACUGCCAAGAUCACAUCACAUUUGUAAAAAUGGUAAGUUAAUGCAUUUGUCAUAUAGUGUUAUGUCUUGGCUUUACCAUAUUUCAUUCUUUAAAAAGUCAUUAAUGGUUUAGAAAUGGGAUGGAAAGUUUACUGAAAAUACCUGUAAGUAACUAUAUUGUUAAUAUCUUCCCUCUGACAGUUAUGACUCUAUAAUCAGUUCAAUGCUUUAUUUUUAAAAAUAUUCAAUGAUUAGUAUUGAAUGCAGCAUUACUAUAUAUUGUACUGAUGCCAAAAGUCAUGUUUUCAUCCACUUAGUGAAAAAAUAGUAAAAUUAAGUCGGAAGAAAUUGCUUAAAAUUUUGUAAUUUGUAUUUAUAAGCCCCAAAUGCAUCAAAUGCAGUAGGAGAACAAUGUAAUACAGCUUGGUACCUAAAAAUAUAGCUAAGUUGGUUUUUGAAUAUAAAACAGUUUAUGAAUAUGUGCAUUUUCUGUAUUGUUAUGAUUUGACUUUUUAGAGUCUAUGCCAAAAUAUAUGGCUGUAAAACAGUACUUUGUAAUUAUAACUUAUGGUCAUAACUGUUAGUGGACUACUUACAGAAGCAGAAACAAGAGCCUGUUAUGAUUGUGCUUUGUGAACAAGCUGAUCUAAUACGUUAAGUACAGAAGUGCUUAGUAUCAUGACUGUCAGAACCAUUCUGCAACUGAGUAUGAAAUCACAGACCAGUGAGGUGAGCUAAUUCAUGUUAAACUGUUAGGCCACUGCUUUGUUAAUGACUCCUCUAAAUGCAUAGUGUGAUGCGAUCCUCUGGCAUAUGCUUUAAUAAAUGGAUGUAUAUUGAGCACAUGCAGCAUUGUAUUGUAUCUUCUGCCUUUUUAUUUCAUUUAUGCAAUAUCAUCUCAUUUAGGAAUAAAAACUCCAGGCUCUUUUGACCAUAUGUAAUAGUCUUCAUAUUAUUUGGUUCUAACAUCUCAUUAAAAGUUUAGAUGUCAGAAUGGUUAUUAUUAAAAAGUCAAAAAAUAACAGAUGCUGGCGAGGUUGUGAAGAAAAAUGUUUGUUUGUUUAUACACUGCUGGUGGGAGUGUAAAUUACUUCAAUUAUUGUAGAAAGCAGUGUGGUGAUUCCUCAAAGACCUACAAACAGAAUUACCAUUCGACUAAGCAAUCCCAUUACUGAGUACACAGCCAAAGGAAUAUCAAACAAACAUUCUACCAUAAACACAUAUGCACGUAUAUGUCCACUGCAGCACUAUUCACAAUAGCAAACACAUGGAACCAUCCUAAAUGCCCAUCAACAGUAGACCAGAUAAAGAAAAUGUGGUACAUAUACACCGUGGAAUACUAUGCAGGCAUAAAAAGAAUGAGACCAUGUCCUUCACAGUGACAUGGAUGGAGCUGGAGGCCAUUACCUGAAGCAAACUAACACAGGAAUAGAAAACGAAAUACUACAUGUUUGUUAUCACAAGUGGAAGCUAAACGAUGAGGACACAUGGACACUAAGGGGGCAACAACAGACACUGUGGCCUACUUGAGGGUAGGAGGAGGGAAAAGAUAAGAAAAAGUAUCUGUCACGCUACGAAGCUUACUACCUGGGUGACAAAAUAAUCUACACCAAAACCCCCGUGACACACAAUUUACCUACGUAAUAAACCUGGACAUGAACCCCUGAAUCUAAAAUAAAAGUUUUUAAAAAAAAGUUCAGAUGUUAAAAUUCAUUCCACAGGUGGUGUGUUCAUGGAAACCACUGUAUAUUGUAAUGACGAGGAAAAUAAGGAUGAACUAAUGUAUCUACCUAUAUAUUGCUAAAUACCGUUUAGUCCCAUGAACAAAAUUCAACAUGCAACAUGGUUAAAAAUCUCACAUGAUAAAAGUUUUCAUCAAUUACUUGAAAAAUUCAUUCUAGAUUUAUGUUAUAAAUAUUUUACAGAACAUUGACUUAAGCUCUUUAGGAGCACAUAUUAAUGUCAUAAUACAUGAUACAUUUGAGUAAAAGGCAGUUAGGAUUUGCAUUGAUCACUUUAAAUUGAGCAAGGUAUUUUUUCCCUGACAUGUUUAAUUGCAUCCAAUUAUUCUGUCUUUUACAAUGUAUACAAUAUAUAUCAAAGCCUAAUAGUGGCAGGGUGAAUUAAGUCUAUUUAUGACUAUCAUAAAGUACAGGUACUAAUUUUGAAAUGAUUAUAAAUUCUGUAGACUCUGUUUUCCUCUCAAAGCACAAGUAUUCCCGUUGUCUUCAGAACAAAGCCUGUUAUAUUUACUUACCCAAAUUAGUAGUCACUCUAAGGUUCCCAGUGAUCUCUGUCAAUUGAGUGUUGCACUAAUGUGUGUAGCAAUUUAUUCAUCUUAUUCUAGAUAAAACACACAAAGGCAAAGCUCUGUUGCUUGUCUAUGGAUAAACCUCACAUUACAGGUCUUUAAAGAUACACGUGUAAAUCAAAUUUAGCAAACACAAAGUAUUUAAACCCAGAGUGGAGUAUUUGCUAUUCGAAGGAAUUUGAAUGCAUUAAGUAAUCAGAUGUCCCCACUACAACCUGCGCUAAUUUAUCUACUUCUAGGAUAAUUUAUAACUUGAAUUUAUCUUAAAUGAGGCACAUUUAUAAAUGACAAUUCUAACUUAAUGUCUUUUAUUUGGUCUUUUUUAAAAACAAUGCGUGAAACAAGAUUUUCUCCUUUUAAUUUCUCUACAUUACAUAAAGAUAUGACUAUACUAGCUAGCCCCUUUAUGGACUACUAUAGCAGCUUUAAUCUUUAUGCUCAAAUAAUAAAUGAUCAUACUUAUACAUGACUCAGGGAAUAUCCUUGAAUAAAUGUCUAAUUCCACCUACUUAGAAAAAUUCUUGGGCACACAGGCAAGAGACUGCCCUCCCCUGUGGAAUGAAUUUUAACUCCCCUGAUGUUACCUGUGUUUAUACUCAAGUCCUUUGUUUGAAAUAGUUGCCCCUUUGCUCUUUUGACUCCCCAGGCCUCCACUGAUCACUCUUCUCUGUGGUUCAGGCUUCUGCAGUGUGAUUUUUAGAAUAAAAAACUAGGAUAUGUGAUAUGAAGGAGAAUCAAUUCCAAUUUGCGAAUGUUAAAUAAUAUAUAUUUAAAAGUGCUCAUGUUUUUUCACAUCAUGACAACUUUGAAAUCAGGAUACAUAUAUAAUCCUUUGGCAUGUUAUGGUUUAAUUGGUGAUUUUUUUCUCCCUUAUUAGUACAUGUUUCUUCUUAUAAUGAAUGACUUCCAGGCAUCAAUAAGCAUAUUUAUUAAAAAGUAUAUAUAAAUCGAUGAAAAUAAAGUAAUGCUUAGUUGUCUAUUUUAAAACAUAGUUUGGCUAGGCACAGUGGCUCACAACUGUAAUCCCAGCACACUGAGAGGCCGAGACAGGCAGGUUGCUUUGAGCUUAGAAGUUCGAGACCAGCCUAGUCAACGUGGCAAAGCCCCAUCUCUACAAAAAAAUACAAAAAUGAGUCAGGCCUGGUGGCAUGUGACUGUAGUCCCAGCUACUUGAGAGGCUGAGGCAGGAGAAUCACUUGAGCCUGGGAAGCAGAGGUUCCAGUGAGCCAAGAUGCAUCACUGCACUCCAGCCUGGGCAACAGAAUGAGACCCUGUCUCAAAAAAUAUGCAUAUUUUUUAAUUUGCAUAUACUAAAAUUCUCUCUUUUGGCAUACAUUUCUGUGUUAUGACAAAUGCGUAGUCAUGUAUUAAUCACAACAGUCAAGAUAUGGGACAAUUCCCUCAUACCUCAAAAUUCCACGUUACCACUUUAUAGACAAACACUUUUCCUACUAUCAACCCUCUGCAGCACUGGUUCAUUUUAGUCCCUCACGUUUUGUGUAUUCCAGAAUGUCAUAUAAACGGAACUAUACAGUAUAUAUUCUUUUGAGCCUGUAUAAUUUCACUUAGCACAAUGCACCAGAGAUUCAUCUACAUUGUGGCAUGUAUAAAUUAUUACCUAGUUUUUUUUGUUGAAUAGUACUGCACUGUAUGAACAUUAAAAAGAUUUCAUUCACCACUUACUACACUUACCUUGUUUGGCAAUAUUAUGAACAAAGCUUUUAUAAACAUUCACAUACAGGAUUUUGUGUAUACUUGUUUUUAUUUUUCUUGGGUGAUUAUCUAUUAGAGUGUGAUUUCUAGGUCUUAUGAUAAGUAUAUCUUUAACUUCAUAAGGAACUUUCAAACUUUUUUGAAAGUAGUUGUAAAAUUUUACAUUUCCAGAAGCAAUGUAUGAGAGUUUCAGUUGCUCUGCAUCUUUGCAAGCACUGGGUAUCGUCAGUUCUUUAUUUUAGUUCUUCUUCUGAUAUACACAAAAUAGCAUCUCAACAUGCCUUUAAUUUGUAUUCAUCUGAGGACUAAUAACAUUGAGUAUCUCUGUGUGUGCUUAUUUGACAUCCAUAUAUUUUGUUUAGUGAAGUAUCUGCAAAUCUUUUGCCCAUUUAUUUAAUGAGUUGUUUAUUGUUGAGUUUGGGGACAUAUUUUCAUAUUCCAUAUACAAACCCUUUGUCAGAUAUGAAAUGUGCAACUAUUUCAUCCCAGUCCGUGGCUAGUCUUUUCAUUUUUAUAACAACCUCUUUAAGAGAACAAAAGGUUUUCACUUCCAUCAAGUCGAAUUUGAUGAAAUCAUUUUUUCUCUUUUAUAGAUCAUAGCUUUGCUACCAUAAGAAUUACUUGCCUCACUCAAGGCCAAAAAGAUUUUUUUCUCCUAUGUUUUCAUAUGGAAAUUUUAUACUUUGGGGUAUUACAAUUUGGCCUAUGAACCGUUUUGAGGUUAAUAGAGGGUGUAAAGUUUGAGUUAAGGUUCAUCUAUAAUUAUUAAAUUACAAUUGAGUAAUUAAUUAGAAACUAAUUUUCAUAGGCAUGUCCAAUUGUUCCAGCACCACACAAUUCAUUGAAAAUACUACAGUUAUCACUUGGAAUUACCUUUGUACCUUCAUCAUAAAUCAAUUGACCAAAUGUGUGUGAGUCCAUUUCUGACAUCUCUAGUCUGUUCCAUUGAUCUGACUCUAUACCUUAUCACCAAUGUGACACUGUAGCAAUUACUGUAGCUUUAUACUGUCUUGAACUCAGGUAGUAAGAGUUCUCCAUGUUCUUCUCUUCAAAACAGUGGAGUAUUCUACUACUUCUCACUCUCUAUAAAAAUUUUAACAGCCAGCCAGGCACGGUGGCUCACGCCUGUAGUCCCAGCACUUUGGGAGGUCAAGGCAGGCAGAUCACCUGAGGUCAGGAGUUCAAGACCAGCCUAACCAACAUGGAGAAACCCCGACUCUACUAAAAAUACAAAAUUAGCCAGACAUGGUGGCGCAUGCCUGUAAUCCCAGCUACUCUGGAGGCUGAGGCAGGGGAAUCACUUGAACCCAGGAGACGGAGGCUGCAGUGAGACGAGAUCACGCCAUUGCACUCCAACCUGGGCAACAAGAGCAAAACUCUGUCUCAAAAAAAAAAAUAACAGCCUACUGGGAUUUUGACUGAGAACUUAUUAAAUCCAUACACCAAUUUACAAACAACCGAUGUCUUAACAAUAUUGAAUCUUCAAUUCGUGGGCACAGUAUAUGUCUCCACUUAUUUACAUCUUCAUUGAUUUAUUACUGUCUUAUGGUUUUCAGCAUACAAAUCCUACCAAGGAUUUCUUCUGUAUGUGUACAAGAGUAUAAAUGUUACUUUGAGAAUAAAAUUCAAAAUCCAAUUGUUUAUUUCCUGUACAAAGAAA